ACCCAAAGAGCAAAAGAACAAACAUCCCACACCUGGGAAGUAGACCCCAGCGCGGUUGCCGCUGGUUGUUCGGGUGGCCCGUUUUUAUUCCCUUAUUUGGCCCCGCCCACAUCCUGCUGAUUUGUCCAUUUUACAGAGCGCUGAUUGGUCUAUUUUACAGAGUGCUGUUUGGUCCGUUUUUACAGAGUGCUGACUGGUGCAUUUACAAACCUUUAGCUAGACACAGAGCACUGAUUGGUGUAUUUACAAUCCUUCAGCUAUACAGAAAAGUUCUCCAAGGCCCCACCUGAUCCAGAAGCCCAGCUGGCUUCACCUCUCGGUUAUAUGCUAAUUAUAUGCAUUAGCACGCUAAGAGAAACGCUCAUCAGUGCCAUGGCAAUUUACAAAUGCCAUGGUAAGGUUCAGAAGUUACCCUGUAUGGUUCAAAAAGCUGGGAAGCCCUCAGCUCCGAGAAAUUGAAAUUGCCCACCUCUUUCCUGGAAAACUCAUGAAUAAUCCACCCUUGUUUAGCACAUCAUCAAGCAAUAAAUACAAGUAUCCCUAGUCCAGCAGCCCAAGCUGCUGCUCUAACAAUGGAGUACCCAUUGUUUCUUUACUUUCUUAAUACACUUGCUUUGGCUUUGCACUGUGCUCUCCCAUGGAUUUUUUCUUGCGUGAGCUCUAAGAACUCUCUCUUGGGGUCGGAUCCGGACCCCUUUCUGGUAACAGAAGCACUGCUUCACGAAGAUCAUGCAGGUCAGUACUUAAUAAGUACAAAAAAGUCUAUAGCGACACUAUUUAUAAUUUUAAAAAUGAUUGAAGUCAAUUAACAUUUAAGUGUUAAAAAGAAAGUAAACAACCCAAAUAUACACAAACAGUAGACUGCUCUGGCUUGCAUACAGAGAGGUCCAUUGCCCUUUUGGGUGGGCCUAAGAAGCACUUCUGGGGAGAGGGGGCGUCAGGCUGUGAUGGCUGCGGGAGGAGUGACUCCUCCCAGGAUGAGGGUCUCCAUCCUCCCAGUGCUCACUCAAGUUCAGUAUUUCCAAGUCCUUCCAGGGGCGUAACGCACGUCAGAACGGCCAUUAGUGUCACAGAUACGUGUCCCCUUGCAUUUCCAGGAAAUGCCCUUGGUUGGCGAACUACAGUCGUGACAGUCGGGCCACAGGGCGUUUUGUGAGUUAUCGUCUUGGGCAAAUGAGUGCCAAAAAAAAAAAAAAAAAAAGACCUGAAGGUGAACAGCAUAGCGGCAGGGUUUGGGAUGAGAGGAGCCCCUUUGCUAGCAACGGCGAGCACUUGCGCGGUACCAGCAAGGGCUGCCCAUGUCUCGGAGGGAAACGUUUGUGUGAGCGCAGGAAUGACCCGGAAGACCUUGGCACGGCUGCAGUUUUCUGGGAAAUGUAAUUUCUUGGUCCGGGCGCCAUGGCCCUUAUAAGUAGAGGGUGUCCCUUGGUUUCGAGUUGUAUCGUUCACCAGAGGACGACUGUGUGCCCCAGGACAAUUUGCGCAUGGUCCUAGCUGGCCGGCUCUAGGUCGACGGCCCCAGGCGGUUAAGCUACUUACAAAGCCGUGACCGGUUUGCCCGCGGCGCACCAGGACACUGCCCAUCUCUAAGAUAAGAACCUGGAAAGGGGACUCUGUUGGCCAUUGGAAAUUGCAGAAUAAUGUCUCAGCGUCAGUACCCAGAGUGUUACCUGGCACCAAAUGGAUGCUUAGUAAGUAAUUGUGGAGUGAAUAAGAUGAGUAAUGAAGAACUGGUGGGGCAGAAUCAUGGCAUGGAAGGUGAAGCUUGCACAGGAGGGGAUGUGACAUUUAGUGAUGUGGCUAUAGACUUCUCUCAUGAAGAGUGGGCAUGCCUAGAUUCUGCUCAGAGGGACUUAUACAAGGAUGUGAUGGUCCAGAAUUAUGAGAACCUGGUCUCUGUAGGUCUUUCCGUAACUAAGCCAUAUGUGAUCAUGUUAUUGGAGGAUGGAAAAGAGCCCUGGAUGAUGGAGAAAAAACUGUCAAAAGAUUGGGAAUCAAGAUGGGAAAACAAGGAAUUAUCAACAAAGAAGGAUAUUUAUGAUGAAGAUUCACCCCAACCAGUAACAAUGGAAAAAGUUGUAAAACAAAGUUAUGAAUUUUCAAAUUCUAAUAAGAAUUUGGAAUAUACAGAAUGCGACACAUUUAGAAGCACCUUUCAUUCAAAGUCUACUCUUUCUGAACCACAAAACAAUUCUGCUGAAGGGAAUUCACACAAAUAUGAUAUAUUAAAGAAGAAUUUAUCAAAAAAGUCAGUUAUAAAAAGUGAGAGAAUAAAUGGUGGAAAGAAACUUUUAAAUUCUAAUAAAAGUGGGGCAGCCUUCAACCAGAGCAAAUCUCUUACCCUUCCCCAGACUUGUAAUAGAGAGAAAAUCUAUACAUGCAGUGAAUGUGGGAAAGCCUUUGGCAAACAGUCAAUCCUCAGUCGCCACUGGAGAAUUCAUACAGGAGAGAAGCCCUAUGAAUGUCGUGAAUGUGGGAAGACUUUUAGCCAUGGUUCAUCCCUUACACGACAUCAGAUAAGCCAUAGUGGAGAGAAACCUUACAAAUGCAUUGAAUGUGGGAAGGCCUUUAGCCAUGGCUCAUCACUUACUAACCAUCAGAGCACUCACACGGGAGAGAAACCGUAUGAAUGUAUGAACUGUGGAAAGUCUUUUAGUCGUGUGUCCCUUCUCAUUCAGCAUCUAAGAAUUCAUACGCAAGAAAAACGCUAUGAGUGUCGUAUAUGUGGAAAGGCCUUCAUUCAUAGUUCGUCUCUCAUUCACCAUCAGAAAAGCCAUACUGGAGAGAAGCCUUAUGAAUGUAGAGAAUGUGGGAAAGCUUUCUGCUGUAGCUCACACCUUACUCAACAUCAAAGAAUUCACAGUAUGAAGAAAAAAUAUGAAUGCAACAAAUGUCUCAAGGUCUUUAGUAGCUUCUCAUUUCUUGUUCAACAUCAGAGUAUUCAUACUGAAGAAAAACCGUUUGAAGUUUAGAAAUGCAGGAAAUCCUUCAACCAGCUUGAAUCACUGAAUAUGCAUUUGAGAAAUCACAUUAGAUUGAAACCCUACGAAUGCAGUAUAUGUGGGAAAGCCUUUAGUCAUAGGUCGUCCCUGCUUCAACAUCACAGUAUUCAUACUGGAGAGAAACCUUACGAAUGUAUUAAAUGUGGGAAGACCUUCAGCUGUAGUUCAAACCUUACUGUACAUCAGAGAAUUCAUACUGGAGAAAAGCCAUAUAAAUGUAGUGAGUGUGGGAAAGCUUUUAGCAAAGGCUCGAAUCUUACUGCCCAUCAAAGAGUACAUAAUGGAGAGAAACCCAAUAGUGUGGUAAGUGUGGAAAAGCCUUUAGAUCAUAUGAAUCCCUAUACAUGUGAGAAAUCUUACAGAAGAGAAGCAGUGUUUAUCACGGUAAACUUCAUUCAUAGAUCCUCCCUUAUUUAACAUCAGAAAAAUGUAUACUGGGGAAAAGUUGUAUGAAGGUGGUGAACAUGGGAGACUUUUAGCAAUGAUGCAGAUUUUUUUAUUAGAGUUUAUACUGUAGAGAAAUCAUAUGAAGUCAAUAAAUGUGGGAAAGCCUUUGUCAGUAUUAAUCCCUUAAUUGACCUAAGUAUACUCACACUAGGAAAAAUCUGUGUACAUGUAGCAAAUGUGGGAAAGACUAUAGGCAAUAGGAAUCUCCUGCAAACUCCUACAGGAGAAAAGUUGUAUGAAUGUGGAAACUUUAGAAAUUGAAGGAAUUUUUCAGUUCCAAGUGCAUCCCUUAUUCUAUAGGAAAUAAACUGGAGACAAAUCUCAUUUAAGAGAUGCAGCAAAGUGUUCACUAAGAGUGUUUAUCUUGCCAGACAUAAGAAGAUGAAUGGUAGAGCAACCUGAAGGAUUUAGAAAUUACAUAUAAAUCUUUGCAGUUAUGCUAUUUGUAAACAGGAUUAUAUAGGAGAGCAAAUAAACAUAAGUAUGCAUUUCUUAGAGCAGUAGCUUGCAGUUUCAGUUGAGUUCUACUUAGAAAUUCUUUUUAGCUAGUGGGCAUGUGAAGAUAUUUAGUCACCCAGAGGAGCCAGUAAAUGUUAUAAUGUUAAAAAUUAAAGCUGCAAAAGAAAUAAAAUGGUGUUAAUAAAAAUUUGGCAUCUAAUAAAAUCAUUUUGUAUAUCAUGAA